AUAGAUCAGCUGGUCACACCUUCUGUUGUUUGGCCCCGAAUAGAUAUUGGCCAGUCUUGGGUCUCUCUGUGGCCCCAGCCCAAGGCUUCCAGGGCAGCUGCCUUUCCUGAGGCAUUGGGCAGAAUUCCUUGUGGCAAGGAGAUCGUAGCACAGAGCCCAGCUGGGACUGCGCACAGUAAUUCAGGGUUGCCAUUGUUCCUCUAUGGGAGUCCGGAGAGCCCAGCCUGUGCUUCACAAGGCUAUGUGGCCCUAGGAAGGUCCUUUUUUAGGCCACAGGCCUUCCAUCUGUGAAAUGGGGGAUGGGUUCAGACUUUAUGCCCUGAAAAGAUCCUUCCAGCCCUGGCCAUCUUGGACUUCUGGAGCUACCCUGGCUCACAGGGGUCUUGUUGCCCUGGGUGUCCCCAGUUCUUGAAAAGAAUCAGCCUGGGAGGGGCCACACCCUGACCAUCCCCCUUUAUCCCUUCUGAGAUGUUUGUUAGGAAGUCUGGGUCCAGGGGAUAUCAUUUCUUGUUCCAUCCAUGCAGGGGUUGCUUACCUCGGGUAGGAAACCCUCAGGCGGUGGCAGGUGCACAGGUAGGGGAGGAUGGAGAGGGCAGUGGUGCCUGAAGCCCUGGAUGGGCGGAGCUGACCCCCCAACACCAACUCUCUCAUGCCUGCUCCUCCCUGUCCCCCCAGAGCUGCCUGAUCAUUGCUACAGAAUGAACUCUAGCCCAGCUGGGACCCCAAGUCCACAGCCCUCCAGGGCCAAUGGGAACAUCAACCUGGGGCCUUCAGCCAACCCAAAUGCCCAGCCCACGGACUUCGACUUCCUCAAAGUCAUCGGCAAAGGGAACUACGGGAAGGUCCUACUGGCCAAGCGCAAGUCUGAUGGGGCGUUCUAUGCAGUGAAGGUACUACAGAAAAAGUCCAUCUUAAAGAAGAAAGAGCAGAGCCACAUCAUGGCAGAGCGCAGUGUGCUUCUGAAGAACGUGCGGCACCCCUUCCUCGUGGGCCUGCGCUACUCCUUCCAGACACCUGAGAAGCUCUACUUCGUGCUCGACUAUGUCAACGGGGGAGAGCUCUUCUUCCACCUGCAGCGGGAGCGCCGGUUCCUGGAGCCCCGGGCCAGGUUCUACGCUGCUGAGGUGGCCAGCGCCAUUGGCUACCUGCACUCCCUCAACAUCAUUUACAGGGAUCUGAAACCAGAGAACAUUCUCUUGGACUGCCAGGGACACGUGGUGCUGACGGAUUUUGGCCUCUGCAAGGAAGGUGUAGAGCCUGAAGACACCACAUCCACAUUCUGUGGUACCCCUGAGUACUUGGCACCUGAAGUGCUUCGGAAAGAGCCUUAUGAUCGAGCAGUGGACUGGUGGUGCUUGGGGGCAGUCCUCUACGAGAUGCUCCAUGGCCUGCCGCCCUUCUACAGCCAAGAUGUAUCCCAGAUGUAUGAGAACAUUCUGCACCAGCCGCUACAGAUCCCCGGAGGCCGGACAGUGGCCGCCUGUGACCUCCUGCAAAGCCUUCUCCACAAGGACCAGAGGCAGCGGCUGGGCUCCAAAGCAGACUUUCUUGAGAUUAAGAACCAUGUAUUCUUCAGCCCCAUAAACUGGGAUGACCUGUACCACAAGAGGCUAACUCCACCCUUCAACCCAAAUGUGACAGGACCUGCUGACUUGAAGCAUUUUGACCCAGAGUUCACCCAGGAAGCUGUGUCCAAGUCCAUUGGCUGUACCCCUGACACUGUGGCCAGCAGCUCUGGGGCCUCAAGUGCAUUCCUGGGAUUUUCUUAUGCGCCAGAGGAUGAUGACAUCUUGGAUUGCUAGAAGAGAAGGACCUGUGAAACUACUGAGGCCAGCUGGUAUUAGUAAGGAAUUACCUUCAGCUGCUAGGAAGAGCGACUCAAACUAACAAUGGCUUCAACGAGAAGCAGGUUUAUUUUUUCCAGCACAUAAAAGAAAAAUAAUGUUUCGGAGUCCAGGACUGGCAGGACAGGUCAUCAGAUACUCAGAGGCUGUAUCUCUGCCCUGCCAACCUUGACAAAUGGCUUCCAAUGUUAGGUUUGCUACAAGAUGGUUACUGGAGCUCUAGCUGCCUAUUUUGUGUUUAGGGAAGGGAAAAUGGAGGAAAGGGGAGAAGAGCAAAGGGCGCUUUUAAAGAGCUUUCCCAAAAGCUCCACCCAAUGACUUCUGCUUCCAUCUCACUAACCACCCACCCCUACCUGGAAUGGAGGCUGGGAGAUGUGGCUUAUUUGCUGGGUACGUGACUAUCCCUAAUAACAAAGGGGUUCUGACACUAAGACAUUAGGGGAGAAUGUUGGGUAGGCAGCCAGCACUCUUUUACCAGAGGGCCUCCUGGUGUUUGGAUUUUGAUCUCAAUGUGUAAAAUGACAGAGAUGUAACAAGCUCAUAGGGUAUCAAUAUCUCUUAUUGUUCUA